GACUUCCGCUGCUGGCCUGGGGCUUCCCAGCCGUCUUGGCGUUGUCCUCUCCAACCCCCGCCGCUCCGCGUAGAACGCCGCUCUCAGGCUGCCGUCAAGCUCCCGCGGCACUCUCCUAGGUGGCCCGACGAGACCCAGAGUGACCCGCGGGACGCCUGUAUCGACCGCGUCCUCUUCCCACCAGCGUGGGAUUCGGUUGAACGUGGAGUCCCCAGCAAUCUUCAGUCUCUCACCAGGGCCAGGGACUCGUCUGGGGCGCGGGGGAAAGAAGCGUGGCGGGGCUGUAGAUGCCGCGUGAGUAGGAUGCAGAUUGCACCGCUGGAGCGCUUGACAACCAACCGAGCGUUGGCUUAGUUUUGUUUUCCCGCACAGCAAGCUCUCUGUCUUUCAGAGGAAGGUAAAGGUGGUGAAAGCUCUAAACUAAAAUUGUAUCGAAAUGGCUGCAGAAAUCGACUUUCUGAGAGAGCAAAAUCGAAGACUAAAUGAAGAUUUUAGGCGGUAUCAAAUGGAAAGUUUUUCCAAAUAUUCAUCUGUACAGAAAGCUGUCUGCCAAGGAGAAGGAGACGACACAUUUGAAAACCUAGUAUUUGACCAAAGCUUUUUAGCUCCUCUUGUUACUGAGUAUGAUAAACACCUAGGAGAACUAAAUGGGCAGCUGAAAUAUUACCAGAAACAGGUGGGUGAGAUGAAAUUACAACUUGAAAAUGUCAUCAAGGAAAAUGAAAGGUUGCACAGUGAAUUAAAAGAUGCUGUUGAAAAAAAAUUGGAGGCCUUUCCCCUGGGCACAGAGGUAGGAACUGACAUAUAUGCAGAUGAUGAAACAGUCAGAAACCUUCAAGAACAAUUGCAGCUAGCCAAUCAAGAAAAAACUCAGGCUGUGGAACUCUGGCAGACUGUUUCUCAGGAGUUGGACAGACUACACAAGCUUUACCAGGAACAUAUGACUGAGGCCCAGAUUCAUGUAUUUGAAAGUCAAAAACAAAAGGAUCAGCUAUUUGAUUUUCAACAACUGACCAAACAACUUCAUGUUACUAAUGAGAACAUGGAAGUGACUAACCAACAGUUUCUGAAAACAGUAACUGAACAAAGUGUGAUAAUCGAACAACUCCGAAAAAAACUUAGGCAAGCCAAAUUAGAGCUGAGAGUUGCUGUAGCAAAAGUGGAAGAGUUAACUAAUGUGACUGAAGAUCUGCAGGGACAGAUGAAAAAGAAGGAGAAGGAUGUGGUGUCUGCCCAUGGAAGAGAGGAAGCAUCAGAUAGGCGUUUACAGCAGUUACAGUCUAGUAUAAAACAAUUAGAAAUAAGAUUAUGUGUGACAAUCCAAGAAGCCAACCAAUUAAGAACCGAAAAUACACAUCUGGAAAAACAGACCAGAGAGCUACAAGCAAAGUGCAAUGAAUUAGAAAAUGAGAGAUAUGAGGCUAUUGUAAGAGCCAGAAAUAGCAUGCAACUCUUAGAAGAAGCUAACCUUCAAAAAAGUCAGGCUCUACUUGAGGAGAAGCAAAAAGAAGAAGACAUAGAGAAAAUGAAAGAGACAGUUUCUCGGUUUGUACAAGAUGCUACCAUAAGAACCAAGAAAGAAGUUGCAAACACCAAAAAACAAUGUAAUAUACAAAUUUCUCGAUUAACAGAAGAACUUUCAGCCCUUCAAAUGGAGUGUGCUGAAAAACAAGGCCAAAUUGAACGAGUCAUUAAGGAAAAAAAAGCAGUGGAAGAAGAACUAGAAAAGCCUUUUCUGCAGAUUUACCGUGAAGGCAGAGGAAAUGAGAGUGAUUACAGAAAACUGGAAGAAAUGCACCAAAGAUUCCUGGUUUCAGAGCGUUCAAAAGAUGAUCUUCAGCUAAGACUUACGAGAGCAGAAAAUAGAAUAAAACAACUUGAAACUGACUCCUCAGAAGAAAUAUCACGUUACCAAGAAAUGAUUCAGAAACUUCAAAAUGUAUUGGAGUCUGAGAGAGAGAACUGUGGGCUUGUCAGUGAACAAAGGCUAAAACUUCAGCAAGAAAAUAAACAGUUACGGAAAGAGACUGAGAGUUUAAGGAAGAUUGCCCUGGAGGCUCAAAAAAAAGCCAAAGUAAAGAUCAGUACAAUGGAACAUGAAUUUUCAAUAAAGGAACGUGGAUUUGAAGUUCAAUUGAGAGAGAUGGAAGACAGUAAUAGAAAUUCCAUUGUUGAACUGAGGCAUCUCCUAGCGACUCAACAGAAGGCAGCCAAUAGGUGGAAAGAAGAAACGAAGAAACUUACUGAAAGUGCAGAAAUUAGAAUCAAUAAUCUAAAGAGUGAGCUGAGUCGACAGAAACUUCAUACCCAAGAGCUGCUUUCUCAGCUGGAAAUGGCAAAUGAAAAGGUAGCUGAGAAUGAAAAGCUAAUUCUAGAGCAUCAAGAAAAAGCCAACAGACUUCAAAGGCGUCUAAGUCAGGCAGAAGAGAGAGCUGCUUCAGCUUCCCAGCAGACAAUCAAAGCCUACCUCAGACUAGAACACAUCAUCUAAUGGAGUUCUGAGCAUUAAAGGGAAAUCAUAUUGAAGAUUUCAACCUUGAAGUUAAUUGUGAAGUUUGUUGCAGAUGGCUAAUGCUUCAAAGGUAGAAACUGUUUUUUCAGUGAUUUGGGUGAAAACAUGAACGUGAGUCCCUGGUGUGACAUUUCCCAUCACAGAUUGCACAGCUGCCAAUGAUAGGCCCUUCCUUUGGCUCCUGGGGACUUAAUUUCCCUAGGGAACUAUUGUGGUUAUUCAACUUUAAGACCUUGUAGGAAGAAUCAGUUGUUUCUCUCAGGGGUCUUACUCAGAGCAAGCAAUAUGGAAGUAAAUAGUCACUAAGGAGAAAUGAGAAGCUUUUAGCAAAAUGUACGAAUAAUUGUUUUUUCUUUUAAACUGGCCAAAUCCUUACAAAAAUUAUAAAUUAGAUUAAGAUAGCUACCCUGUUUUGGAUCCUAAUCAUUAUAAUCUACAUGAGAAUGCAUAAUUCACACCAGUUUUGCUGUUCCCAACAUAAAGAAAAAGGUGCAUUUCACUAUAUGCUAAUUUCUGCAUGUAGUGGAUGUACAAAAGAUUGUUUCAGGCAGGAAACAAUCUUUUCAGAAAUGAGAAUGAGAGUGUAGGCCCAGUUCUGCCAGUACCUACUGCUGUGAUCUUGGCCAAGUCUUAAGGUGUAUAAUGCAGAUAAUAUUUUUUUGCCCUACUGUCCCAGAGUUCUGUGAUCAAAAGAAAGCAUUUAAUGAAACUGCUCUUUGAAAAAUUAUUUUUAAAAAUUAUUUAAAGGUUGUAUUAAAAAUACAACCGUCCCAUCAUUCAGGAAUAUUUUUUCACCUCAGAAAGCUCAUUAGUUAAAAUAUUGUAAACAUCAGUGUCUUGUUCCUAAUAAAAAUAAUAGCCUACCACUUACUAAAUGCCUAAUAUAUGCUCUCUGUAAGGUGCUCAAUGGACUUGCUUUAAAUAAUCACAACUACUUCAAUAUCUAAGUUACUAAGAUGUUAUCCUCUUUCUGGGAAAACUGAGGCUUAAAACGGUUAAGUGACUUGGCCAAUGUCAUGUGCCUGGUAAACUAUAGUUUAGCCUUUAAAUACAGUUCUCUCUGACCCUGAAGUCUACGUUGUUUCAACGAUUCUGUUUUCAGAUCCAAAACUGUAUUCUGGAAAGAACUCCAGGUGGGGAAGACUAAACUCAAACCGUUAUUUUUCAGUCUCGCCAUCAGAGUUGAGCCAGAAAGCAGCCCAGUGAAUCUGUGCUCUGCACAAAUUUGAUAUGUUCUCUACAGUUCUCAUUCCUGAUUUAAAGUGGAAGACAGUAAACAACUGAUUCAGGACUGCUAAGUCAUAUAUACCUUUAAAUAUUUAGCAAAAGCAGAUUUCAAAAGACACUUAAAAUGUAUUGCAAAAUGUACAGCAUUUAUUCACAUACAGACAAAAAGGCACAAUUCUACUAAAUAGUUCAACAAAAAAAUACAGCUGUCCUCAACUAGUUUUAUAAAUACUUUCAAAAAGGGGGUAGAAAUAAAUACAGGAUUGGGUCAUGUAAUAUAAAAUAGUCAUCUCUACAUAUACUUUAAUUUGAUUUUUAACUCUUCAUGCACCUUUUUUUUUUUUUCAAUUUUAGCUGAAUGGACACCAAGCUAGGCACAUAGUGAAAAAUCCUCUGUACAAGGUUACAAAUGUAAUGACAAGUUUGUCCAUUUCAAAAUAAGAUUUGUACACAACACAUAAAACCCUUCAUUUAGAUCUUGUGUUUAUAACCUAACAAAUGACAUUCCAGGCAACUUUACAAAAGUUUAACUAGCCUACAUUUUGACAUAAUACAUUAAUCAUAAUCAAAGAUAUUUCUUGGUCAGGAUGCACAAGGAAAGAUAAAGCUUAAAAAAAACAAAUGCAAAUGGUUCCAUACUAAUAGAACGCAAGUGGGUGUUUGGGCUGGUUGCUGCUUAUGGCCACCUCAUAGAGAGUUCCCAGCAUGACAUGAAACUAACUCACAAAGCUAUCAUUAUACUGUCAGAGAAACCGUGCUCUAUCCAUUUGCAUUUCGAAGCAGGAAUAAAAAGUGUGGGCUUUUUAUUUUUGUGUGUUUUGUUUUUGUGUGGGUUUUUUUUAAUAUUUUUUGUUUUGUUUUUGUUUUGUUUUUUUUGGUUCAGCAUAACUUGGAACAUUUGAAAGCUUUUCAACCUAAAUGUGGGGAAAAAACAGGUAAGGCAUUAUUUUUGCACAAAACUAGCAUUCCUAAUAGUGCAAAUGAAUCUGAUACCUCUUAAAAUGGUGAGAGGUCAUACACUUACUAGAUUAAUUUAGAUUUUCUUUCUAUGGCUUGACAAAUUAUCCCUCUAUAAAUUCUACUCUCACCCAGAGCUGUUGCUGUAAUCAAAAGAUAACUGUAGAUAAAGUCCAACCUUCUCCUGUAUCCAGCAAAAGGUUUUUGCUCAUAUGCAAAAAAAAUCUAAUUUUUAAAUUAUCCUACAAGUGAAUAUACAACUUGGAUUCAUAAGAACCUUCUAUUAUCUGCAGCAACAAGCUGAUCUGGACAGCAGUCUUUCAAAAUGAGCCCCAUAACUCAAAAAUAGUCAGUCAAUCUAAAAACCUGCAUCAUUCUUCCCCCUCCCCUGAAUUAGCUACUAAAAUGUCCUUGAAAAGUUAAGACUUGGUUUGAAAAUGUCGUACAUACAAUGGGGAUGUAUCAGAUCUACUAUUUGAUCAUCUGAUAAAACUUGCAUAGCAAGAUGGGAUUCAAUAAGCCUUUUUUGUUGUUGACAAUCAUCUGGAAGACUUGAAAGUUAACUGCAGAACUCCUCAAAGCAUUAUUCAUUAAGUAUCAUAAUGUCCCUGCCAUAUGGAAACAGAUGUAUAAAUGAAUCAGGAAUCUGAAUACUGGUAUUAACAAACUAAGGAGAAUUUAGGGGAAGUCGGGCUUGUUCCAAAGGCCCAUAAUUCUGUAUCUCAUUGCUAUUUAAACGUUCCUUCCUUAAGUUUGAUUCACAACCACAUUGAAUUCCAAAGAAAAUUAACAGGACCUAAACACUAUCCACUGUCUUAAUACAUACGCACUAUGGGGAGUGCAAAAACAAAACAUUGUACUCAAAUUUAAUGCUAAAUUUAUUAUUGCUGAUAACUUAAUAGUUAUUGCCAUUUGCAAUUAGAAAGUCCAAGUUACAAAUUAGAGUUUAGAACUCUGACUACAGAAAACCUAUUCAAGGGUACACUUCAGUCUCUUUCCUGUAUAACCUUGGUCAAUAGUAAGAGCUUAUCGCAACUUAUUGCCUUUCUAUUGUUUUUAAAAUAUAACCUAUUUCGCUUUUUUCUCUUUUUUUCUUUUUUCUUUUUUUUUUCUUUUUUUCUUUUUUUUUUUUUUUUCCUUUUUCUUAAGGAA